AUGUGGAUGCUGGGAGAAGUAUGUGAGAUGGAAAAGUUGUUUCAUGGCAUCCAAGAAGUGAAUGAUCCUCAAGGUGUAGCAGAGGAAUUUGUAGGAGAGAGGGAUGAUUGACAUCUUCGUGUAGCCCUCCAUCCAUCCCAGUUAGCAUGGAGGGAUUUUAGGGCUACCAUUGGCUGGGUAGUGGAGUGUUGACCAAUCACAGCUCAGGGGCGUGAUUGUCUCGUCCUGGGAUCGCGAGAGGUGUAUAUACAGGGAGGCCAGGCAGCCUGGAGUUAGUCGACCGUUGCGAGACGUUGAGCUGCGGAAGAUGAGUCCAAAGCCGAGAGCCUCGGGACCUCCGGCCAAGGCCAAGGAGGCAGGAAAGAGGAAGUCCUCCUCUCAGCCGAGCCCCAGUGACCCGAAGAAGAAGACUACCAAGGUGGCCAAGAAGGGAAAAGCAGUUCGUAGAGGGAGACGCGGGAAGAAAGGGGCUGCGACAAAGAUGGCGGCCGUGACGGCACCUGAGGCGGAGAGCGGGCCAGCGGCACCCGGCCCCAGCGACCAGCCCAGCCAGGAGCUCCCUCAGCACGAGCUGCCGCCGGAGGAGCCAGUGAGCGAGGGGACCCAGCACGACCCCCUGAGUCAGGAGAGCGAGCUGGAGGAACCACUGAGUCAGGAGAGCGAGGUGGAAGAACCACUGAGUCAGGAGAGCCAGGUGGAGGAACCACUGAGUCAGGAGAGCGAGGUGGAAGAACCACUGAGUCAGGAGAGCCAGGUGGAGGAACCACUGAGUCAGGAGAGCGAGGUGGAGGAACCACUGAGUCAGGAGAGCGAGGUGGAAGAACCACUGAGUCAGGAGAGCCAGGUGGAGGAACCACUGAGUCAGGAGAGCGAGGUGGAAGAACCACUGAGUCAGGAGAGCCAGGUGGAGGAACCACUGAGUCAGGAGAGCGAGAUGGAAGAACCACUGAGUCAGGAGAGCCAGGUGGAGGAACCACUGAGUCAGGAGAGCGAGAUGGAAGAACCACUGAGUCAGGAGAGCGAGAUGGAAGAACUACCGAGUGUGUAGACGGCCAAGUACUCCCCUAUCUCCGAGAGCAGCGACUAAGUUCAGGCCCAGCCGCCAGACCUCAGAGAUCUCACCAGCGGGGUGCUUGCCAUUCUGAUGAUAAUAAAAUGAAUGUGUUGCAAAUUGA